ACAGAUGGAGUGAGUCAGUCCAAGCUGCUCAACCUGUUAAAUGUCUUUUCUUUGCUAACUGGAGUAUAAGCUUAAGAACAAAAGUAGGACUUGUCUAUGUUUGUAAUGGGAUUGCAGACAGCGUGUUUUGUAAUGUGAUAGAUGGAUCUGACUUCCUAAAUUAUUGGCAGGCUUAAUUUACGUAACAAAUGAAUGUUCCACCUUUUUUUUUUUUUAAACCUUUGAAAGGGGAAAUUAGUACACUGCUGUCAAGUAGCUUUUCUCACAUACUGUAUAGGGAGUGAAAUGAUUGUUUAGAACUGCUGGUCAUUACAGAAUGUUCCUCACAUAACAAAGGAACUUCAGGAUUUGUCUCCAAGUCCAUGUUUAUGGUCAGGAUAAACCAGAAGAACAUUAAACCGUUCAGGAGAUGUGCGGCGGCACAGCGAACACCACAAACCAGCCAGAGAGCUGGCAAGACUCUGCCAGAUGUGUGAGUGAUGCUGUUCCUGGUGCUGGGAGGAUUUACAGGGCGCUUUUAUGCACAAAGAUUAAAAAACACACCGGAGUAGACAGGAGCACUGACCACACGGAACUCGACAACAGUUGGUCAUGUUCGGAGUUUGACCUGAAUGAGAUUCGCCUGAUAGUUUACCAGGACUGUGACAGGAGAGGCAGACAAGUCUUGUUUGACUCUAAAGCUGUUCAAAAGAUUGAGGAGGUGACAGCUCAGAAAACAGAGGAUGUUCCUAUUAAAAUAUCAGCCAAGUGCUGCCAGGGAAGCAGCAGUGUCAGCAGCAGUAGCAGCAGCAGCAUCUCUUCCCACAGUUCUUCUGGGGGAUCUUCACAUCAUGCUAAGGAACAGCUUCCAAAGUACCAGUACACAAGACCAGCUUCCGAUGUCAACAUGUUAGGGGAAAUGAUGUUUGGCUCAGUUGCCAUGAGUUACAAAGGCUCCACCUUAAAGAUACACUACAUACGUUCUCCUCCACAACUGAUGAUUAGUAAAGUCUUCUCUGCUAGAAUGGGCAGCUUCUGUGGAAGUACAAAUAACUUGCAAGACAGCUUUGAGUACAUCAACCAAGAUCCUAAUUUGGGAAAACUGAACACAAAUCAAAAUAGUUUGGGUCCUUGUCGUACUGGAAGUAACCUAGGUCUGCUGCAAGCAUGCAGCAGCAAACUGCUGCAGGGGGUAGCUGAAGGAGGACCUCUCCGGCUCACCCGGAGUGCUUCUUUCUUUGCAGCACACAGCACACCAGUUGAUAUGCCAAGCAGAGGACAGAAUGAAGACAGGGACAGUGGCAUUGCUCGAUCAGCCUCACUAAGCAGUCUUUUGAUCACACCUUUCCCAUCUCCAAGCUCCUCUACAUCUUCUUCCAGCAGUUACCAGCGCCGCUGGCUUCGAAGUCAGACAACAAGUUUGGAAAAUGGCAUCAUCCCAAGAAGGUCAACUGAUGAGACAUUCAGCUUGGCUGAAGAAACCUGUAGCUCUAAUCCAGCUAUGGUUAGGAGGAAGAAAAUUGCCAUAAGCAUCAUCUUUUCCCUAUGUGAGAAAGAAGAAGCACAAAGGAAUUUCCAGGACUUCUUCUUUUCUCAUUUUCCCCUGUUUGAAUCUCACAUGAACAGGCUGAAGAGUGCAAUUGAAAAGGCUAUGAUCUCCUGUAGGAAAAUAGCAGAAUCAAGUCUCCGAGUCCAGUUUUAUGUCAGCCGUUUGAUGGAAGCUCUGGGAGAAUUCAGAGGAACUAUCUGGAACUUAUAUUCUGUUCCAAGGAUAGCUGAACCUGUAUGGCUUACUAUGAUGUCCGGCACUUUGGAAAAAAACCAGCUCUGCCAGCGCUUUCUCAAGGAGUUUACACUUCUGAUAGAACAGAUAAAUAAAAACCAGUUUUUUGCUGCCUUACUGACUGCGGUGUUAACCUACCACCUGGCCUGGGUCCCAACUGUCAUGCCUGUGGAUCACCCUCCCAUCAAAGCCUUCUCAGAGAAACGUACCUCCCAGUCAGUGAACAUGCUGGCCAAAACACAUCCGUAUAAUCCUCUUUGGGCACAGCUGGGUGAUCUUUACGGAGCCAUAGGCUCUCCAGUGAGACUGACUCGCACCGUAGUGGUAGGGAAGCAGAAGGACUUAGUCCAGCGAAUACUUUAUGUCCUGACCUACUUUCUCCGUUGCUCUGAGCUACAAGAGAACCAGCUGACCUGGAGUGGCAAUCAUGGUGAAGGUGACCAAGUUUUAAAUGGGAGCAAGAUCAUAACAGCCUUGGAGAAAGGAGAGGUGGAGGAGUCUGAGUAUGUGGUCAUUACGGUGAGGAACGAGCCCGCUCUUGUACCCCCCAUCCUACCACCAACAGCAGCAGAGAGACACAACCCCUGGCCGACAGGGUUUCCUGAGUGCCCAGAGGGCACUGACAGUAGAGACCUGGGUCUUAAACCUGACAAAGAAGCUAACAGGAGGCCAGAGCAGGGUUCUGAGGCUUGCAGCGCAGGGUGCCUGGGGCCAGCAUCAGACGCUUCCUGGAAACCUCAGAAUGCAUUUUGUGGGGAUGAGAAAAAUAAAGAGGCACCGCAAGAUGGCUCUUCAAGACUUCCCAGCUGUGAAGUUUUGGGGGCAGGAAUGAAGAUGGACCAGCAAGCUGUCUGUGAGCUGUUGAAAGUGGAGAUGCCUACAAGACUGCCAGACCGGUCAGUGGCCUGGCCUUGCCCUGACAGACAUCUCCGGGAGAAACCUUCCUUAGAAAAGGUCACUUUCCAGAUUGGAAGCUUUGCAUCUCCAGAGUCUGACUUUGAAAGCCGCAUGAAAAAAAUGGAGGAACGGGUGAAGGCCUGUGGCCCCUCCUUGGAGGCCAGUGAGGCUGCUGAUGUGGCUCAGGACCCGCAGGUUUCUAGGAGCCCUUUUAAACCUGGCUUUCAGGAGAAUGUUUGCUGUCCUCAGAAUCGGCUUUCAGAGGGGGAUGAAGGCGAGUCUGACAAGGGUUUUGCAGAGGACAGAGGCAGCAGAAACGACAUGGCAGCAGAUAUUGCUGGGCAGCUCAGCCACGCUGCUGACUUGGGCACAGCCUCCCACGGUGCAGGAGGAACGGGAGGGAGGAGGCUGGAGGCCACUAGAGGUUUGUAUGUGAAGGCUGCGGAAGGACCUGUGCUGGAGCCUGUUGCCCCCAGGUGUGUCCAGCGGGGCCCUGGCCUCGUGGCUGGUGCGAAUAUCCCCUGUGGGGAUGACAACAAGAAGGCCAACUUCAGGACUGAAGGAGACAUUCCCCGAAAUGAAAGCUCAGAUAGCGCCCUGGGAGACAGUGACGACGAAGCCUGCGCUUCAGCCAUGCUAGAUCUGGGUCACGGUGGUGACAGGACUGGAGGGUCCUUGGAAGUGGAGCUGCCUCUGCCAAGGUCUCAGAGCAUCAGCACCCAGAAUGUAAGGAACUUUGGCCGCUCACUUCUGGCGGGCUACUGCCCCACAUACAUGCCUGAUCUUGUGCUUCAUGGGACCGGCAGUGAUGAGAAGCUGAAGCAGUGCCUGGUGGCCGACCUUGUCCACACAGUCCAUGUGGAACAAAAGGCAUUGCAUGUUAUCUUUGGCCUUGAGCAUCUCCUCUGUGAAGACCAAACAUCAGGCACAGGCUAAACAGGCUAAGUAUAUUUAUGUGAAGUGGGAAAAAAACUCAGUAGUGAAGCAGAUGUCAACAUAACCUCCCUCAAUGGGGAGGGCUAAGAGAUGAGGAUAGGGCCAUCAGAAGCUGGGGAAAGCCAGCCCAGUGUACACGUGUGUGGCCAAACGUUCCUAACCCCACCCCUGCUUUGUGGUCACAUGCCACCCCUCACCAGGAUACUCCUGGGAUGAAACUAUGAAGUUGCUUUUGUCCCUAUAAUAUCAUAAUUAUUUAAUAUCAUAAUUUCUCUUUAUAGUUAUGAACACCAUAUAGUCAUUUAUCAUUUCAUGAGUCCAUGCAUCAAUGACCCCUGUAAGAAAAAUGCCCUCAUUGUAUAAUGCUAAGUUGUCCAAAACGAUGUCUGAUGCUUUGGCAAUUUCACAGGCUGUAUUUAUGUGUGUUUAGUAACUGCCUAUAACAUUAAGGCACCUUUUCUGUCCGCUCCUAUUGUUUAUAUUCACACAUGCCAAACUGUGAGUUGUUUUUUUUUUUCUGCUCUGCUAUCAUUUUGAUUUCUAACAAUAUUGGUGUUGGUUAUUGGACCUUCCUUCCAUGAAGCCCAGUGAGCUGCUUCUGACAGAGGUACCAAGAGACUACAGGGGAACUAAUGGGAUUGUCCUCAGUGACAUCAGUUUUACCAGCUGGGGACUUUGUUUGAAUGCCCUGGAUUUACUCACUGACCACUCUGGAAAUGCAAUCUAUUGAUUGAUAACCCUCCUUGAACUUAUCUGUAAAACCAUUCAUGAAAUAUUUUAUGUUUCCAUAGGCUGGCAAGUUCUCAUUUUUGUGUGUUAGAUUUUCAUGGUGACCCUCUGGCUCUAUAAUUCUUUUAUUUGAAAAAACACAACCAUGUUUACUCUGUCAUUACUCUUCAAGCUUUUUCGUAUUUCAUUUUCCCUUCCUUUUAGAAGGAGUGUUUUCACACUGUAGCUUUUCUCAUUUCUUUAUGCAAUCACCCUGAGAGAUCGAAAGUUAUUAAGCAUAAUAACCUAUAUUGUGUCAAAUUGUGGGUACAUCCAAAGUGCAGCCAUGCGUGGGUGUUAAUAGGAAAUUCCAAAGGGUUCAUAAAAAUAUCUUCAGAAGUUUAAUACAUUCAGAAUAUAUCCAAUUAGCAUUAGUGGAUUUCUAAUUUCACUUGACACAUUCAUCAUAAUGAAUUUUGCUUUUGAAGUAGUGUUCUGUUUAAACUGGCGCUCUGGUCUAUGGUAGUGUUUUUUUUUUUUUUUUUAAAAAACAGGCUUACUUUCAACAUCCAUUUACAAACAUUUGUUGAAAAAUAUUUUAGGAGUAUUUGUUUAAACAUUAUUCCGAAUUUACUGCUCCAUAAAGCCUAGUGAAUAUUUAAAUUCUUGAAUAUGUUGCCAGAAAAAGAAGCAGAGAUCCAAAAACAAGUAUAUGACCAGAGUUAGAGCUGAAAUAAUAGCUUGUUGAAGAAGAGAAAAUUGUAAUAAAUUGCUUUAUCAAACUUGCUUUCAAAACCUGUUUUUUAAGUUGGGCACAGUGGCUCACGCCUGUAAUCCCAGCACUUUGAGAGGCCAAGGUGGGUAGAUCACGUGAGCUCAGGAGUUCAAGACCAGCUUGGGCAACAUAGCAAGACUUCAUCUCAAAAAUAAAAUAGCGUUAAAAAAAAAAAAAGAAAAAACAAACCUAUUUUUUGAACAUUAAUUUCAGUGCUCAUGCUAGAUUUCAGCAGGCUUUGGUACUCAUAAUUCUUUUUAGAGAAGGAUUUUUAACUGUUUAAAAGCAAUUGAUUCCAGUUAUUGAUCUCUUUUCUAGACCUGUGCACAAUUUGGAUUUAAUAAUCUGUCUUAUGUAAAUUAAAUGUGGUGGUUUUUUUUGUUUUGUUUUGUUUUUGUUUUUGUUUUUGUUUUUUUUGAGGUGGGAUCUUCCUGUAUUGCCCAGGCUGGACUUGAACUGGGCUCAUGUGAUCCUGCCUCAUUCUCCCAAGUAGACAGGAUUAUAGGCACAGGCCACUGUACCUGGCUCUAAAUGUACACUUUUAUAACUGCUAGUUUGGAGUUUUUCUCUCAUUGAGAGAUUGCUUUGUAAUGCUUCCAAUGUUAAGAAUUUUUUUGUACUUUUCUUAUCCUAGUCUCUUAUGAAAGAAAGAUAUAGUAACUACUUCAUCAAUUUUCAUUUUUAUUACUGACUUUCACAUAUCAAGAUUCAGAAGUUCUUUAAAUAUUUAAACACGUAUUCUUGUUUAGUCCAUAUACUACCUCUUUUCUGUCAUUUGAACUCUCUCUGCCUCCUAAUAUAUAGGUUAUACAGCUGCCUUAAAUUAGUGUAAAGUAAUACGGUUUCAGUUUUUUUCUUGCCACAUCUUGUGCAUUCUUUCCUCUGUUUUCCUUUUGACUUUAAAUGGAAAGAGAGCAGGCGUAUGCGCCAGCAGCAUUCUAUGCCUGUGACUCCUGAGUAGCCUUUUCCCUCUCCUUUUUCCUCUUGUGUCUGGCCUGUGAAUACAGCUGACUGUAUACAGGGUUACUGUUGGGGUUAUUGUGGGGCAGUGUAAGGUGAUGAAGAUCUCACUGACUUAGUGUUGAUGGCUUGAGUUUGAGUCCUGGUAUUACCACUCGUUUGUUGAUAAUCUUAGGUAAAUAAACUGGCAUUGCUAAGCCCCAGAAAAAUGUAUUUAGUGGAACAGAUGAAAUAUGAUUCAGUGGUUAGGAAGUUAACUUCUGAAGACAGACAAACCUAAGUUUGAAUCAUGGUUCACCCCUUAGUGGCUUUGUGGCCUUGGGCAAGUUUCUUUAAUUUUCUUAUCUAUACUGUGAACAGUACUUACAUCAUAGGUUUGGUCUGAAGAUUCUGUGAGAUAAUGCAUAUCAAGUGGUUAGCACUUUGCCAGGCACAUUGUUAAGUGCCCAAUAAAUGUGGGCCAAAUGUGAUAGCUCACCCCUGUAAUGCCAGAGCUUUGGGAGGAUCCUUUGAGAUCACCCUGGGCAAUAUAGCAAAAUCCCAUCUCUAGCAAAAAAAAAAAAAUAGCUAGGCAUGGUGGCACAUGCCUGUAGUCCCAGCUACUCAGGAGACUGAGGCAGAAGGCUUGCUUAAGCCAAAUGUUCAAUGCUUCAGUGAGCUGUGAUCAUUGCCACUGCACUCCAGCCUGGGUAACAGAGCAAGACCUCAUCUCAGUAAAUAAUAAUAAUAAUAUAUGUAAAAGUGCUUUGUAAAUGAUACAGCAAUAUAUCAUGUUUUUAAUAUGGGAGAGCAGAAUGACAACCAUUAUUUUCGUAAAAAUGAAAAUUACUGUCAGAGAUAAGAAAGCUAUAUAUGGGCCAGGCACGGUGGCUCAUGCCUGUGAUCCCAGCACUUUGGGAGGCCGAGGUGGGCUGAUUGCCUGAGCUCAGGAGUUUGCGACCAGCCUGGGGAACACAGUGAAACCCCGUCUCUACUAAAAUACAAAAAAAAAAAAAAGUUGCCAGGUGUGGCAGCGGGUGCCUGUAGUCCCAGCUACUUGGGAGGCUGAGGCAGGAGAAUUGCUUGAACUCGGGAGGCAGAGAGGUUGCAGUGCGCUGAGAUCAUGCCACUGCACUCCAGCCUGAGCAAUAGAGCGAGACUGUCUCAAAAAAAAAAAAAAAGAAAAGAAAGAGAAAAGAAAGCUAUAUGCGUAUGUACUUAAAGUUCUCCUAACUAGUCAAUGGCCUUGUCAAUCCCAGGGGACUACUGUUGGGAAUGAUUGAACAGAACCUGUACACACAUUCAUUGAGUGCUAAAAGCAUUCACUUUUGCUUUGCCCAGGAGCAGACUGGACAGCUCUAACUCUGCAGGGCAGGGUCAUCAAGACCAAAAUUAACACUACGUUUUGAUGUUUUUUAAAAAACAACUAUGCUCCAGGGCUUCAAGCAUUUUACAGAAUAAUUUAUAAGAUGAAGUAACCAUUGGAUACAGCAGCCUCUUCCAUUUAAUUUUAAGCGUAGCAACAGAUUGACUCCAGAAAUAUCAUGCAGGAAUCAGUAGCACAGAUAAAGAGCUUUGCUAAAAGCCUGGCUGUGAUAUAUAUAUAUAUAUAUAUAUAUAUGCUCAUGAAUACCUAAUUAGUCCAUGCAGUGCAAUCAACCUGUAGGACUAUAAAAGAACAGCAAGUCCCUUCAAAUGGUAAAUCAUUACUUAAGUAACACAGAUAACAUUAAAUACCUCAGGUCAGCAACAACCUUAAAAUCAAUAGGAUACAAAGAAAACAUCUAUGUAGGACAAAUCCACUAUUUUGGAACAUCUCUCGUUGUUUUCUUUUCCCCAUGUUUGGAUAAUAAACAUGGCAGUGCCUCAGGCCUCUAGCACUGUCUUCUAUAGCCACAGCCCUCAAUACAACACUACCUAUGUCCACUGGCCUAUGGAGCACUUUUAAAACUACAUAUUUUGACCUAUAAAUGGGUUUUGAUUACCAGUUUUUUUAAUGAUAUAGAACUAAAAUCAUCACACAUUAGGCUUCUUAUUGAUUAGUGAAACCUUUGUAUUAUGUGUGUGUGUAUUUAUACACAUGUGCACACAUGUCACACUUGUAUGCAUAUGGCAUGUCAUGCCAGGUUAUGUCAUAUAAGCAUGUAUGCCAGGUCAUGAUGUUAAAAUGUAUUUCUUAUCAUGGAUUGUGGUUAAAAAAAAUACUGAUCUCUGGGUAUCCCCAACUCCAAUCUGAAAUCAUUGUGAUUCUCUCGCCUUCUCAAUGUGACUAGUCUUUUUAAAGUUCCUUUUGAUCUUCCCAAAUGGCAUCCCUGUGUCCACUUUACCCACUUCCACCGCCUUGUGCAGUGCUGCAAGAGGACUUUCUAAAGCAUGAGACAAUCAUUUACUCUUUUGCUUGAAUAGCUUCCUAUUUUCUAAGAGACUAAACUGUAAACUCCAUAGCUGGAAUUGCCCCUUUUAUGUCCUUCAAAUAUACACACAUACCCCUGUAUCUCCUCUUAUGCCCCAGUAACACUGUUUGCCAUUCUUUAAAUAGUCCACCUUUCCUCACACCUCUCUGCCUAUCAGAUUAUGCUUUCUUUGCCUAGGACACUAUUGAACAAACUUUUUUACAUUUUUGAAGACCCAUUUCAUAUGUUGCCUCUUCUUCAAAAUCAUUCCAGGCCCCAUAUCCCUGUUCUGUUCCAGAUGUGUUCCUCUACUAGGGCUUCAGGUGCCUUGAAGCAGAAAGCAGGGACUUUAUUUUCCUUAUAUUCCCAGCACCUUGCCUGGUGCCUGGCACAUAGAAAGUGCUCACUAACGUUAGUUGACUCUUCCCCAUAAAACUGGGGUUAGAGUCAUGUGUGUCUAUUACUUUAGUGUGGCCCUUUCUUCUGAAGUAAAGAGAGAUGGGAGAUGAUCUUUCUUUAAAGAAACUUAAAGGGGAAGAGUAAGAUGUUUAGACAUGCCUGCAGCUCUGUGUGUUCAUUGUCGUUACCUAAAGGAAAAUAAAAGCUUAUUAUAGGUC